GGAAGCGGCUGCGGUUCUCGCCGGUUCUCAGCCGGGGUUUGAUAGUUGUCAGGAGGAUUCGACGUUCAGUGCCCAGGGAUGUGGAGAGUUCUUGGAGUCUCUGCGGAGUCCCUGGGCCAGAUCUCACAGUGAAAGCUGCAGGAUCUUCCUUCUGACCCCAGCAGUCCCCGUUGAGUCCACCGAUCCCACUGGAAUUAUAAAGUUGUCAGCAAGAAAGCCCCAGGGCUGAAGUCCAAGUCCGUCGGGAACAUGCCAGCUAACGAGGACGCUCCCCAGCCAGGGGAACAUGGCAGUGCCUGUGAGGUAUCAGUGUCAUUUGAGGAUGUGACUGUGGACUUCAGUAGAGAGGAGUGGCAGCAACUGGACUCUACUCAAAGACGCCUGUACCAGGAUGUAAUGUUGGAGAACUACAGCCACCUGCUCUCAGUGGGGUUCGAAGUUCCUAAACCAGAGGUCAUCUUCAAGUUGGAGCAAGGAGAGGGGCCAUGGACAUUGGAAGGGGAAGCCCCACAUCAGAGCUGUUCAGAUGGGAAAUUUGGAAUUAAGCCUUCCCAGAGGAGAAUUUCUGGGAAAUCUACAUUUCAUAGUGAAAUGGAGGGUGAAGACACAAGAGAUGAUUCAUUAUACUCUAUUUUAGAAGAAUUGUGGCAAGAUGCUGAACAGAUAAAGAGAUGUCAGGAAAAACACAACAAACUUCUGAGUCGCACUACUUUCCUCAAUAAGAAAAUAUUGAAUACAGAGUGGGAUUAUGAAUAUAAAGACUUUGGAAAAUUUGUUCAUCCAAGCCCAAAUCUCAUUCUUUCACAGAAAAGACCCCAUAAACGUGAUUCAUUUGGGAAGAGUUUUAAGCAUAAUUUAGACUUACAUAUUCAUAAUAAAAGCAAUGCAGCAAAGAACCUGGAUAAAACUAUUGGGCAUGGUCAAGUUUUUACCCAGAACUCUUCUUAUAGUCACCACGAAAAUACACAUACAGGAGUGAAGUUCUGUGAACGUAAUCAAUGUGGAAAAGUCCUCAGCCUCAAACACUCACUCAGUCAAAAUGUGAAAUUUCCCAUUGGAGAGAAAGCAAACACAUGUACUGAAUUUGGGAAGAUCUUCACCCAGAGGUCACAUUUCUUUGCUCCUCAAAAAAUUCAUACUGUGGAAAAACCUCAUGAGCUUAGCAAAUGUGUAAAUGUUUUUACACAGAAGCCACUACUCAGUAUAUAUCUGAGAGUUCAUAGAGAUGAAAAACUCUACAUAUGUACUAAAUGUGGGAAGGCCUUCAUCCAGAAUUCAGAAUUAAUUAUGCAUGAGAAAACUCAUACUAGAGAGAAACCCUAUAAAUGCAAUGAAUGUGGGAAAUCAUUUUUCCAGGUGUCAUCUCUACUCAGGCAUCAGACAACUCAUACUGGAGAAAAACUCUUUGAAUGCAGUGAAUGUGGUAAAGGCUUCUCCCUGAACUCAGCCCUCAAUAUACAUCAGAAAAUUCACACUGGAGAGAGACAUCACAAAUGCAGUGAGUGUGGGAAAGCCUUUACCCAAAAAUCAACACUCAGGAUGCAUCAGAGAAUUCAUACAGGAGAGAGGUCCUAUAUCUGUACUCAAUGUGGGCAGGCCUUCAUCCAGAAGGCACACUUGAUUGCACAUCAAAGAAUUCAUACUGGAGAGAAGCCUUAUGAAUGCAGUGACUGUGGGAAAUCUUUCCCUUCUAAGUCACAACUCCAGAUGCAUAAGAGAAUUCAUACAGGAGAGAAACCCUAUAUAUGCACUGAAUGUGGGAAGGCUUUCACCAACAGGUCAAAUCUCAAUACUCACCAGAAGUCUCAUACUGGAGAAAAGUCUUAUAUAUGUGCUGAAUGUGGGAAGGCCUUCACCGACAGGUCAAAUUUCAAUAAACACCAGACCAUUCACACUGGAGAGAAACCCUAUGUUUGUGCUGAUUGUGGGAGGGCCUUCAUCCAGAAGUCAGAGUUGAUUACACAUCAGAGAAUUCAUACUACAGAGAAGCCUUAUAAAUGUCCUGACUGUGAGAAAUCCUUCUCCAAGAAACCACAUCUCAAAGUACAUCAACGAAUUCACACAGGGGAGAAACCAUAUAUAUGUGCAGAAUGUGGGAAAGCCUUCACUGAUAGGUCAAAUUUCAAUAAACAUCAGACAAUUCAUACUGGAGAUAAACCGUAUAAAUGCAGCGACUGUGGAAAGGGGUUCACCCAGAAAUCAGUUCUCAGUAUGCAUCGCAAUAUUCAUACAUGAAAGUAAUCCUGUUUCUUGAAAAUGAGAGCCUUAUAAGGCUGACAAAAGUCAGGUCUAACUAUAUAUUAUAAAAUUCAUCCAAGACAGAUCCUAUAUGAAUACAUUGUAUAAGGAAAAGCAUCAGGCUAUCUCACUUGAGAUGGAAAAAAAUUAUUCAGAAGAAACUCUCUUAAAAAUGCAUUGAAGGAGAGAGAAUUUGCACAGCCUCAUGAAAUAUAGUAAAAGUCAUACUGGGAAAAAUGUUGUCAGUUUGGUGUGUUAGGAAAAGCCUUCCUAUAGAAAGUAUUAUAAGUUAAAUUGUUACCAAAUUCUUUAUAGGAAGGAGAGUGCAAAAUUAUGUAAAUGAUGGUCAGGUUUACUGUGUUAUAUUAAGCAAUUUAAAGUGAUAACAAAAUGAAAGGUAGUGCAGCAAAAUAAUAUAACUGGUGAGUAGACCUACUUUCAGUUCCAUAGGGUGUUUGUGGCAGAACACAGUGCAGAACAGGAGGAAUAUUACAUUUUUUUUCAAAUUUAGAAUAAUUAUGUCCAUCAAAUGUUUCUUACUGAAUAUGUCUAUCAAAUAUGUUUCUUAUUGAAUAUUUCUAUCAAGUGAAUCCACAAUUUAAAAGUCACUUUGGUUUUAUAUAUACACACAUCUGCAGAUAUAAUUUUAUAAGAACACACAAAUAUAAUCCUGUCAUUCGUACUGGUUUCCAUGACAUAGUAUCUUGUUUUCUUUCAUUGUGGUACAAUGCAAAGUAGCCACAGAUUCCUCCCAUCCCAAGUAGCGUCUCUUUGUCUACUACUUGACUUUGAACUUGGCCACGUGACUUUCUUUGGCCAAUGGAAAUUAGCAAAGAGAAUCAAUAAGAAGCUUGAGAAGUGUGCAAAGCCUGCCUUGAAGCUUACCCUCUCUUGCUGCUCUUUGCAAACCUGAAGAAUCUCAAAUUGCCCUACUCGGGGGUGAGGAGCCACCACAUGGAGCAGUGGUGAGCCAGCCUUGCUGAGGCCCCUUAGACCAAGUAGCCUGCCAAUUGUCAGAAUUGGGAGUGAGGUUUUCCAAGACCUCUAGCCCCAGCUGAGCCAGCCUAGCCCAGAAGAGCCAUACCAGUUAUUCCAGCUGAUUUACAGAAUUGUGAGAUAAAUAAAAUGAUGAUAGUUUUAAGCAACAUGAGUUUUGGGGUUAGUUUGUUGUACAGAAAAUGCUAAGUAAUAUUUGAAAGUAUAUGUUUGGGGGAGGGGGCAUAGUGGACCAAAACGUGACAAGUGGCAUUGGCUUUGGGUCUGAGUGGCACGUAGAAACUGGAAAAACAGUGAGGAAAACUGUUUUUCCUCAAAUAACAAAGGUUGGAUAGUUGGCAACCCAUGUUAUUUAGUAGGGAAAGAUACAGAAAAACAGUCAUCACCAUACUCUGUGGGAAGAUAGAGAAUGGACCAAACGAACUGGUGGAUCUGGCUAAGGAGAUUUGCAGCAGAAUAUGGGAAGUAUCAGUUUGCUUCUUUUAGCUGCAUAUGAUACGAUACAGAAAGAGAGAAAUGAACUAAAGAAAUAACUGUUUCUUUGGCAAGCAGAAUUCAGAAGAAAUAUGGAAAAGCCAAGGAUUGCUGGGUUGAAAAAUAAUGCUUUCACAUCACUAGUCUCUCCAGCUAUCUAACUAUUCGCAAGGUAAAAAAUGGCCUCAGGGUAAAGAUCAAAUCAUGGUUGUGUCUGUAAGACUCUUUAUUACAGUGUGUGAAAUAGUUCAGUUGGUGCUUAGGAGACCAUCUCAGCUAAACUUAAGGGCUUCUAAAAAUCUUCAUGACGUUGUCCCAUAGAAGCCUGACAUACUACUCAAAGUGGAGAGAGACCUAUCUUAAAAAGAAUUGCUGAUGUGGCAUUUGGGGAAAGGAGUAGAUCCAAACCAGAUUCAUAGGAAACUCACAAAGUUUUUAAUAGAGUUUUACUAGUAAAACUACCUCCAGGUUGGACUUCCAGGGACUGAAACAGUUCAAAAUGAAAAGUGGCCUCUGGAUUCCCCUCCCUAACUUCUAUGAAUAGGAUACAAGCUGAGAAAGUUACUCAGAUGCAAACACGGUCCAUUUCUUAUGGAAAAUGAAGGGCAUCUCAGAGGGAAGACCCAAGAACAAUAUAUUAAAAUGAGCUGGGGAGCCGUUCCCAGGGAGAACUGUGCCCUAAUCAAGAAACGUAUCUGCCCCUGGAGCCAAGGGAACCGACAACAUUUGCUCUGUGGGAUUUCAGAAUCGUUAUGGAACAGUGACUGAUAUGUGCCUCAUGGUCCUCCUCUUUUUGAAUGGGAGUGUCUAUUACAGUUAUCCUGUACCUAUCCCACCAUUGUAUAUAUUGGGUGUAUGUUGGGGGGCAUGUAACUUGUCAUUUAGCUCACAGGUAUCUGGAUCAAGAAACUGAAAAACUGUACCCAAGGAACCUCAGCCACACCUGAACCUGAUACAGAAGACUUGAGAUUCUGGAUUGGAGCUUGAUGCCACAAUUUUGGAUGAGAAAUUUGGAGGUCCUGGAAUAGGGGUGAACACAUUUUGCAUGGGGUGGUAAUGUGAAUACUUUGUGACCAGAAGACACACUGUGUUAGGUAGAAAAAUGCUACAGAUGUCUUCAUCCCUGUAUAUGUGUCCUUCUUCAGUCUUUAUUUCUCUUUGUGUUUCAGUUAGGAUAAUUUCUAUUGAUCUGUCUUCAAAUUCACUGAUGUUUUUUCUCUCACCCUGGCUUUGUCAAGUCUACUGCUGAACCCAUUGAAGGCAUUCUUCAACUCAGUUAUGUUUUAUUUUUAUUUGUAAUAUUUCCAUUUGAUUCUUACAAUUUUCAUAUAUCUGCUGAAAUUCCCCAUCUUUUCAUGCAUGUUCAUGUUUUCCCCUUUACCCUUUGUCUUAGUCAGUUUGAGCUGCUAUAAUAAAGCACCAUAGACUUGGUGGCUUAUAAACAACAGAAAUUUAUUCCUCACAGUUCUGGAGCCUGGAAGUCUGAGAUCAGAAUCUAGCAAGGUUAGGUCUUGGUGACGGCCCUCUUCAAGGUUGCAAACUGCUCACUUCUUGCAUUUUCCCAUGUCUACAGCUAGAGAACUCUUUGGGAUCCCUUUUAUAAGGGCACCAAUCCCAUUCAUGAGUUCUCCACCCACAUUACCUAACUACCACCCAAAGGCUCCACCUCCUAAUACCAUCACAUUGAGGAUUAGGAUUUUAACAUAUGAAUUUUGGGGGGGAUGCAAUCAUUCAGCCCAUAAUACCCUCUAACAUAUUAAUCAUAGUUAUUUUUAACUCCCUGUCUGAUAGUUCCAACUACUAGGUCAACUGAGUCUAGGUCUGUUGUUGUCUUCUCUUGCUCUUUUGCAUCUAAUAAUUUUUGGCUGAAUGUCACAGAUGUUGUAUGUAGGACAGUAGAAACUGAGGUAAAUAGUAAUUAUUCCUGGAAACAGCCAUGGUUGCCCUUUUGAUAGGCCAUUAGCAUGGGGAGAUUGAAUCCAUCUAAUCAGGAGUUGGGCUGAGUUUGUGUUUCUUUGUUGCCAGUGUUACCUUUGCUGUACCAUAGACUUAAAAUUCCUCUAUUGUUAUCUUAUGCUUGAGGUAGGCACUGGUUUGCCCAGAGAAUUUUUAUUUUUCCCAGACCACACUUGCCUUUAGGCCUGUAGGCCUUUCCUGUGUGCCUGCAUCUCAGGGAGGGUCUCUCUCCAUGUUGUUGCCUCUAUGUUAGUAGUAGACAACUGUUAUUACUUGGUUCUUGCUGACCUGGUGAGUUGGGGGGCAGGGGUUGUCUUGGGCCAGCCUCAGUUUUUGUCAGGCCAUGAAUCCCUGGGUCUUGAGGGUGGGAUUUUUUAGUGAUCCUGCCCUCUUCCACUGGUAGAAGGCCUUUAAUGAUCUGGGCCCAGGAUGAUUUCCUGCCCUUUUAUCAUGGGUGGAAUUUUUUUUUCCAUUUCCCUCACUCUAGUCACAGUGAAUCUUUAACUGUGUCCUGAGGGCAACAGGGUUUGCUGCACUUCUUUUAGUGGCUUAAGGAUUUUGUUCUGUAGGGGAGUAGGGUUUCAUUGGAGCUUUGUGCCAUUUCUAUGUUAACAGCAGCCCCCUUGCAGGCCUACCCCAUGGAGGUAGGCUUUCUCCAGUCUUCUUCCUUGUCCCCGUGUUUCUUGAGAGCACUCAGUGGAUGACUAUGGAGAAGAGCCUGCAAGCAGAGACCAACUACCCUUAGGUCUACAGCUCUCAUGAGUCUCCCGCACUCAGCCUUUAGCAAUUCAUUAAAAAUUCUUGUUGAAUUCUUACUGCUUGUAUAGUGGCCUCAUCUUCCUUCCUGCUGUACCACAGAUGGCCCAGGAGAGGCACUUGUCUUUUAUUAUAUUUCAAGCUAGUUGGUUGCUCUGUAAUCUUAGCUCUCUGAUGGGUUCGAGAAAACUUAUGUUUUUGCAGAUUACCCAGCUUUGUUCUUGUUAUAAAGAUGGGAGCAGUGUUCUUUCCAGAUGUCUACAUGCUAGGCAGAAACUAGAAGUCUGGACAGUCUCCAUGGUCUCCUACUAUCAGAAUAUGUGCCCUUUUCAGUGUGACUUUGCCACUUCACCCAUCAAGAGGUAGAAUCUAUUUCUUCAACCCCUGCAACUGAGCUUGGCUAUUUUGUUGGCCAAUGGGACAUUAACAAGUAUGAUACAAGCAGAGGCUUGAGAAGUGCCUGCACAAUGAGGCUUGCCCACUUUUGCAGCUCUUUGGAAUCCUGAACCCAUGUGUGGAAAAGCCUGAACUGUGCUGUUGGAAAAUGAGAGCGAUCACAUGGAGCAGUAAUGGAGCAAAGACCAGCCAUCCCAGUUGAGAUACCCUACACCAACCAGAUUUUCAACUGCUGGACAUAUGAAUGAAGCUAUCCUAGGCAUGCAGUCUUGGUCAAGGCAACUUUGGCUGGCAGUCUCUGAGAUGACCCUGAAUGAUCCCCACCUCCUGGUAUUCUCACUCUUAUAUAAUCCCCUCCUCUUGAGUUUGGACUGGAAUUAGUGACUUGGUUCUAGUGAAUAGAAUGAGGCAGAGGUAAUGGGAUGUCAUGUUCAAGAUUGGUUACAAAAAGACUGUGGCUUCCAUUUUGGGUGCUUGCUUACUCUCUCAGAUGGCUCAUCAUAGGGGAAACCUGCUGCUACAUCAUGAGAUAGCCCUGUGGAAAGGUCCACAUGAGUGAACUUUGAAGCAUAUCCUCCCCCAGUUUAGCCUUUAGAUGAGGACCACAGCCAAAUAGCUUGACUGUAAGCCAGAUAGCUUGACUCAUGAGGGACCUUCAGCCAGAGGCAUCUUUUGAGCCAUACGAAUUCCUGACCCAUAGAAACUGCAAGACAAUAAAUGUUGUUUUAAGUUGCUAAAUUUUAGGGUAAUUUGUUACACAGUAAUAGGUUAAUAAUACACUGGCCCAGAUUAGGAAGGUUCUGCCAUCCAUCCCAGCCAUCCCAAACAACUACCAGAAUAAUGGAUUAAAACGUUAACUGUUUUAAGUCACUAAGUUUUGGGCAGCAUGAUAACAACCCAGCAAAAAGCUAACUGAUACAUUGAUUAUUUAUUGCAUUUCUUCCUCCACUAUUCUUCUCUAACAGAUGACCAAUACUAAUAAACUACUGUGAACACUUUCAUGUUUUAAUCUCUGCUCUGUGCUCAUAAUCAUAUAUAGACAUACAUACGUUCCCAUGCUUGUAAUCAGAAGUUAUAUAAGAUUGUUUCCUCCUUUGAUUUUCAAAAAUGGGAUCAUAACAUACAACCAUCUCUGCAGCUUGCUUUAUUAUUAUUCAACAAUAUUUGUUUUGAAUGGUUGCAUGAUAGUUUAUGGGGUGGAUGUACAAUAAUGUAUUAAACUAUUUGCAUUGUUAAAAUUUAUUCACUCCCAUUUUCAACCCUUUUUUGUCACUGGGAACAAUGCUGCUAAAAAUAUUAAAAGAUAGUUUGCAUAGUGGUUAGGUAGAUAGGCUCAGGAACCCAUCUGCCAGGGUUUCAAUCCUGGCUCUACCAAUUUACUAGUUUAUGUGACCUUGGGAAAGUUAGUUAACCUCUGUCCUGAUGGUUUUCAUCUAUAAAAGAUGUACACACUACCACCUAUCAUAGAUUUGACUAAGAAGCAUAUUUCUUUCCUCGGGCUGCUAUAACAAAGUACCACAAAUUGGGCAGCCUAAAACAGCAGAAAUUGUCUCAUUGUUCUUGAGGCUGGAGAUCCGAAUCACGGUGUCAGCAGGGUCAUGCUCCCUCUGAAGGUGCUAGGGAAGGAACGGUUCCAUGCCUCUCUCCUAGCUUUUGAGAGCUUCAGGUGUUAUUUGGCUUAUAGAUGCAUUAUUCCUGUCAGAUGGCUGUUUUCUCCCUGUGUUUCUUCACAUCAUGUUCCCUCUGUGUGUCUGGCUCUCUUUCCAAAUUUCCCCUUUUAUAAGGACACUAGUUAUAUUGGAGUGGGGUUCACUUUAAUGGCCCCAUUUUAACUUAAUUACCUCUGUACUCUAUUUCCAAAUAAAAUUGUAUUCUGAGGUUCUGGGGAUUAGGAUUUCCACGUAUCUUUUUUGCAGGUACACAGUUCAUUAACAAGAAGUUAAUGCAUAUUGUGUAGAGCUCUUAGAACUAUGCAUGGAGAGAAUUUCUUAAUGGGUAUUAGAUACACCUCACUUCCUGAGCCCGCACAGGUCCCCCUACAACUCUCUGUGCUUGGGACACUGAGGUGGGAUUUGAGAGCUUGUUUCCGGCAUCUUAGUGUCAUCCAGCUAUCUAAAGAAAAUGUAGGGAGUAACAGGAAAAGCAGGCCUAAGACCAAAGCUUGUGCUUUGGGUCGAGAAGGAUAUGCCUAUAGAAGAUAAUGAGAAGGAGCAGCCAGAGAGGUAAAAACAUACCAGGUGAGCAAGGGGCUCAUAGAGAACAGUGUUUCCAACAAGUGUUUUAAUGGAGGACUUGUCCAAAUUAGACAUCAAUUCAUAUGAGGAUGGAAAAUUGGUUCUUGAUUUUAUGACACAGAGGUUGUUGUUGGCUUUGAUGAAUGCUAUUUUGGAAGUAAAUUUAAACAAAGCAAUUGAGCAAACUCAGAGGAAUUUCUGAAUUCAGGUGGUGUUACUUCACCAUGAAGCAAUUUUUCUCAUAGAAAAAUAUCAAGCCAUUGGACUAGAUUAUUCUGUCGUUUGGGUUAUACUGAGAAAUAAGAGUUGGCUAAAGUAGAAAUUACAUGAGAUUUGGAAGGUCAAAGGGAAGGAGCAACUAUUGCUGUGAAAGUCUUUGAAAUUAGAGACAGUGAAGGACAGAUGCAGAGGUACCCAGCAGGUUCCAGUUUUUCCUAUCUUCCACUCUAUAUCCAGCCCUUCUUUCCAUCUUCCAGCCCUGCUGACCAACAGUAGCCCCAGGUCUACCACCAGAUGCUUGGCUGCAGGCUCACAAAAGCUUCUCAUGGACUUCUCCACCAGCUUCUCAUGGCAGUCCCACAUCAGCAGCUAGAUGUGCCUGGCUUCUCAGAUUUUCCUGAAAGCUCUGAUUUAUCCACCCAUGCUAAUGUCUCAAAAGGGCUGGUUUAGUGAUUUCUUUAGUCUUCUAACUCCCCCUUCUAAACCUUCCCCAGCUACCUCUAUAAAUUGUGCAUGCAUCCCUUAUUCCAUAAUGCUCAUAGUUAUUAUGCUUCCCUGAUUGACAUAUUUAUACUUUCUUUUCCUGAGAAUUUGGUAGAUGCUGCUCUUCUAAAAUUGAGUGAUGUUAUUAAGAAGUCUUAGACAAACUUGCUCUCUUUUUUCUUGUAUAUAAUGUGCCUUUCUGCCAUAUGAUUCUUUUUUUAUUCUUGAAGUUAAGGAUCUAUGGAAGCAUAUGCUUUGGUCCUGAUCUUUGUGUAUUAAUUUUACCUGAGUUAUAGUGAGCCAUUCCAAUCAUUCAUUUCAAGGAAGUUUUAUUUUGCUUAACAUUUUUUCUGAUCCAUUUCUUCUCUUCUUCAGGGACAUCAAUUAUGCAUAUGUAAGAUGUCUUUGUCACCUUCUACAUUCAUCUUCUACCAAUCAACAUCCAUUUCACAUCAUUAUUCUUUUCAGUUUUGUGUGAUUGACUCUAGCCUUGUCUUCAGAGACAAUUCUCCUUGAAUCUCAUGUUCUUCAUGUUUAGACAUUAACAAGCAAUUUGCUCAGAUUUAUUUACAUUCCAGGAUAGUAAAGAUAGAGAAUGUCUCCCUCCCUGGAGACUUUCCCAGAGAAGAUUUGGUUGCAUUCCAGGUUAAUAAAGAUUAUAUAUAUAUAUACCCAAAGAAGAGGAUGGACAAUAAAACAAUAUAACAUUAUUUCCCUCACAUCUUAAUUAUGUGUAUUUUCAAUCAUGUAGAAAUAUUGAAAACACAGUACAACCUAUAUAACAUCCAUCUAGAUUUAACAAUUUAUAUGUAAUUUUUCCUGAAAUACCAGUGGUAAGUUAUAGAUAUAACAUUAUAACCAUAAAUAAUUGAGCAUUCAUCUCCUAAAAAUAAGGACAUUCUCCCACAUACCUGGAAUAUCAUUAUCAAUCUAAUUCUAUGAUAUAUCCAGUCCAUUUCCAAAUUUCUCCCAUUGUCCCCAAAACAUAUUUUACAGUUUUAAUGAGGUAGAAUUAGCAUACAGAAAGUGGAACUUGUUUAAAGUGUACAAUUUGAUGAGUUUUGACGUGUGCACCUUUCCAACCAUCAUGACAAUACAAAUAAUGAACAUAUCAAUCACCCCAAAAAAGUUUCCUUAUGCCUCUUUGUCAUUCAGCCCCCUUUCCCCACAUUCUUCCCACAUCCACAGGCAAUCAUGGAUCUGUUUUCUAUUGUUAUAGAUUAGUUUGCGUUUCCUACAAUUUUAUACACAUGGAAUAAUACUAUAGGUACUCUUGUUUGGCUCCUUCCAUCCAGCAUAAUAAGUUUGAGAUUCAUUCAUGUUGUUAUAUGCGUCUAUGUUCAUUCCUUUUUAUUGCUAAGUGUUAUUUCAUUAUAUGGACAUACCAGAAUUUGUUUAUCCAUUCAUGUUUUGAUGGAAAUUUGUAUUUCCAGCUUUUGGCUAUUACAAAUAAAACUGAUGUGAACAUUUGUUUACAA